CUCUCUCUUUCUCUCUCUCUGUCUCUUAGCCUUGCAGCCGUUUCCCUCUGCGAUUCAUGUAAGUGUGACUCGAUUUCAGGGAAAGGGAACUCGCGUGGGCUGAGGAGACCGGAGUGGACGGGCUGGGGAAGGCACCGUGAUGCCCGCAACCCCGUCCCUGAAGGUGGUCCAUGAGCUGCCUGCCUGUACCCUCUGUGCGGGGCCGCUGGAGGAUGCGGUGACCAUUCCCUGUGGACACACCUUCUGCCGGCUCUGCCUCCCCGCGCUCUCCCAGAUGGGGGCCCAAUCCUCGGGCAAGAUCCUGCUCUGCCCGCUCUGCCAAGAGGAGGAGCAGGCAGAGACUCCCAUGGCCCCUGUGCCCCUGGGCCCGCUGGGAGAAACUUACUGCGAGGAGCACGGCGAGAAGAUCUACUUCUUCUGCGAGAACGAUGCCGAGUUCCUCUGUGUGUUCUGCAGGGAGGGUCCCACGCACCAGGCGCACACCGUGGGGUUCCUGGACGAGGCCAUUCAGCCCUACCGGGAUCGUCUCAGGAGUCGACUGGAAGCUCUGAGCACGGAGAGAGAUGAGAUUGAGGAUGUAAAGUGUCAAGAAGACCAGAAGCUUCAAGUGCUGCUGACUCAGAUCGAAAGCAAGAAGCAUCAGGUGGAAACAGCUUUUGAGAGGCUGCAGCAGGAGCUGGAGCAGCAGCGAUGUCUCCUGCUGGCCAGGCUGAGGGAGCUGGAGCAGCAGAUUUGGAAGGAGAGGGAUGAAUAUAUCACAAAGGUCUCUGAGGAAGUCACCCGGCUUGGAGCCCAGGUCAAGGAGCUGGAGGAGAAGUGUCAGCAGCCAGCAAGUGAGCUUCUACAAGAUGUCAGAGUCAACCAGAGCAGGUGUGAGAUGAAGACUUUUGUGAGUCCUGAGGCCAUUUCUCCUGACCUUGUCAAGAAGAUCCGUGAUUUCCACAGGAAAAUACUCACCCUCCCAGAGAUGAUGAGGAUGUUCUCAGAAAACUUGGCGCAUCAUCUGGAAAUAGAUUCAGGGGUCAUCACUCUGGACCCUCAGACCGCCAGCCGGAGCCUGGUUCUCUCGGAAGACAGGAAGUCAGUGAGGUACACCCGGCAGAAGAAGAGCCUGCCAGACAGCCCCCUGCGCUUCGACGGCCUCCCGGCGGUUCUGGGCUUCCCGGGCUUCUCCUCCGGGCGCCACCGCUGGCAGGUUGACCUGCAGCUGGGCGACGGCGGCGGCUGCACGGUGGGGGUGGCCGGGGAGGGGGUGAGGAGGAAGGGAGAGAUGGGACUCAGCGCCGAGGACGGCGUCUGGGCCGUGAUCAUCUCGCACCAGCAGUGCUGGGCCAGCACCUCCCCGGGCACCGACCUGCCGCUGAGCGAGAUCCCGCGCGGCGUGAGAGUCGCCCUGGACUACGAGGCGGGGCAGGUGACCCUCCACAACGCCCAGACCCAGGAGCCCAUCUUCACCUUCACUGCCUCUUUCUCCGGCAAAGUCUUCCCUUUCUUUGCCGUCUGGAAAAAAGGUUCCUGCCUUACGCUGAAAGGCUGAAGUGGGGCGCGCGAAGGGCGGCGAAGCGGAGACGGCGGCUCUCCGGGAUCCAGCUCCGCCCCUGGCCAGUGUGCGGCCCGGGGGCUCCCUGUGCCCGCGUGAGGCGAGAGAACAGGGGACUUGAGUCUCGAACAGCGGUUGUUUUUACUUUAUUUAUCUUAGGCCCUCAGCUCCCUGACGUCCUGAGCCUCCCUGUGACGCUCUGGCCUUCUCUGUACCUCAGAGUGCAGAACCACAGACGGCUUCGGCUGUGCCUAGGGCAACAGCCAACCUAGGAGCCAGCGGGCUUUCGGGGAAAAAAAAGAAAAAGACAUCUAAAAUAAAAUGUUUAAACUGUUUCAAAA